AGUUCUCUGAUGUAAAGCCUGGCAGUCCCGGCCUGCUUGGGGGCACCUGGACCCCUGCCAGGGAAGGGGUCCUCAGACUUGAGGUUGCCAGCUCAGAUGUGGGGCUGCUGAUACUAGGUGACUGGACUGAUGUUCUGUUCUAGAUGAAACUCCUUGAGGGGACCAUUUGAAAAGGCUUGAUGUGCUGCCCAAAGCCCCCUUCAGAGCUGACUUCUCCACCCCCAGCUGCCGUGAGCCUUGGCUGCUGACAGCUCAUAGCUGAGUCCCUCCCGUGAAGUCACCUUCUGCUGAAGGGUACAUCCUCUCCCAAGGCGAAGCUGGUCCGUUACAUUUGUAAGCAGAGGCAGUGCAAGCUGAGCGUGGCUCCCGGUGAGAGGACCCCAGAGCUCAACAGCUACCCCCGCUUCAGCGACUGGCUGUACACUUUCAACGUGAGGCCGGAGGUGGUGCAGGAGAUCCCCCGAGACCUCACGCUGGAUGCCCUGCUGGAGAUGAAUGAGGCCAAGGUGAAGGAGACGCUGCGGCGCUGUGGGGCCAGCGGGGAUGAGUGUGGCCGUCUGCAGUAUGCCCUCACCUGCCUGCGGAAGGUGACAGGCCUGGGAGGGGAGCACAAGGAGGACUCCAGUUGGAGUUCAUUGGAUGCGCGGCGGGAAAGUGGCUCAGGGCCUUCCACGGACACCCUCUCAGCAGCCAGCCUGCCCUGGCCCCCAGGGAGCUCCCAGCUGGGCAGAGCAGGCAACAGCGCCCAGGGCCCACGCUCCAUCUCCGUGUCAGCUCUGCCCGCCUCAGACUCCCCCACCCCCAGCUUCAGUGAGGGCCUCUCAGACACCUGUAUUCCCCUGCACGCCAGCGGCCGGCUGACCCCCCGUGCCCUGCACAGCUUCAUCACCCCGCCCACCACACCCCAGCUGCGACGGCACACCAAGCUGAAGCCACCACGGACGCCCCCCCCACCCAGCCGCAAGGUCUUCCAGCUGCUGCCCAGCUUCCCCACACUCACCCGGAGCAAGUCCCAUGAGUCUCAGCUGGGGAACCGCAUUGAUGACGUCUCCUCGAUGAGGUUUGAUCUCUCGCAUGGAUCCCCACAGAUGGUACGGAGGGAUAUCGGGCUGUCGGUGACGCACAGGUUCUCCACCAAGUCCUGGCUGUCGCAGGUCUGCCACGUGUGCCAGAAGAGCAUGAUAUUUGGAGUGAAGUGCAAGCAUUGCAGGUUGAAGUGUCACAACAAAUGUACCAAAGAAGCCCCUGCCUGUAGAAUAUCCUUCCUGCCACUAACUCGGCUUCGGAGGACAGAAUCUGUCCCCUCGGACAUCAACAACCCGGUGGACAGAGCAGCCGAACCCCAUUUUGGAACCCUCCCCAAAGCACUGACAAAGAAGGAGCACCCUCCGGCCAUGAAUCACCUGGACUCCAGCAGCAACCCUUCCUCCACCACCUCCUCCACACCCUCCUCACCGGCGCCCUUCCCGACAUCAUCCAACCCAUCCAGCGCCACCACGCCCCCCAACCCCUCACCUGGCCAGCGGGACAGCAGGUUCAACUUCCCAGCUGCCUACUUCAUUCAUCAUAGACAGCAGUUUAUCUUUCCAGUGCCAUCUGCUGGCCAUUGCUGGAAAUGCCUCCUUAUUGCAGAAAGUUUAAAGGAAAACGCUUUCAACAUUUCAGCCUUUGCACACGCAGCCCCGCUCCCUGAAGCUGCCGACGGUACCCGGCUCGAUGACCAGCCGAAAGCAGAUGUGUUGGAAGCUCACGAAGCGGAGGCUGAGGAGCCAGAGGCUGGCAAGUCAGAGGCAGAAGACGAUGAGGACGAGGUGGACGACUUGCCGAGCUCUCGCCGGCCCUGGCGGGGCCCCAUCUCUCGCAAGGCCAGCCAGACCAGCGUGUACCUGCAGGAGUGGGACAUCCCCUUCGAGCAGGUAGAGCUGGGCGAGCCCAUCGGGCAGGGCCGCUGGGGCCGGGUGCACCGCGGCCGCUGGCAUGGCGAGGUGGCCAUUCGCCUGCUGGAGAUGGACGGCCACAACCAGGACCACCUGAAGCUCUUCAAGAAAGAGGUGAUGAACUACCGGCAGACGCGGCAUGAGAACGUGGUGCUCUUCAUGGGGGCCUGCAUGAACCCGCCCCACCUGGCCAUUAUCACCAGCUUCUGCAAGGGGCGGACGUUGCACUCGUUUGUGAGGGACCCCAAGACGUCUCUGGACAUCAACAAGACGAGGCAAAUCGCUCAGGAGAUCAUCAAGGGCAUGGGAUAUCUUCAUGCCAAGGGCAUCGUACACAAAGAUCUCAAAUCUAAGAACGUCUUCUAUGACAACGGCAAGGUGGUCAUCACAGACUUCGGGCUGUUUGGGAUCUCAGGCGUGGUCCGAGAGGGACGGCGUGAGAACCAGCUAAAGCUGUCCCACGACUGGCUGUGCUAUCUGGCCCCUGAGAUUGUACGCGAGAUGACCCCCGGGAAGGACGAGGAUCAGCUGCCAUUCUCCAAAGCUGCUGAUGUCUAUGCAUUUGGGACUGUUUGGUAUGAGCUGCAAGCAAGAGACUGGCCCUUGAAGAACCAGGCUGCAGAGGCAUCCAUCUGGCAGAUUGGAAGCGGGGAAGGAAUGAAGCGUGUCCUGACUUCUGUCAGCUUGGGGAAGGAAGUCAGUGAGAUCCUGUCGGCCUGCUGGGCUUUCGACCUGCAGGAGAGACCCAGCUUCAGCCUGCUGAUGGACAUGCUGGAGAAACUUCCCAAGCUGAACCGGCGGCUCUCCCACCCUGGACACUUCUGGAAGUCAGCUGAGUUGUAGGCCUGGCUGCCUUGCAUGCACCAGGGGCUUUCUUCCUCCUAAUCAACAACUCAGCACCGUGACUUCUGCUAAAAUGCAAAAUGAGAUGCGGGCACUAACCCAGGGGAUGCCACCUCUGCUGCUCCAGUCGUCUCUCUCGAGGCUACUUCUUUUGCUUUGUUUUAAAAACUGGCCCUCUGCCCUCUCCACGUGGCCUGCAUAUGCCCAAGUAACUGCUCUCAGAGGAUCCCACUAACUGAGCUCCCUCCAAGGCAGUCUGGGCAGCUUCUAACUACCUUCCUGGACAUGACUGAUUGCUCCCGUGUUCUUCUGAGGGCUGGUCUUGUUUUUGUUUGGGUGGCUCUGUCUCACUGCUAACACCUUAGUGAGAUGCCUUCCACCCUCCUGAGCACACCAGCCUCCCACUGGGUGUGUGCCUAGUGCGGGGCGGGCGGAGGUUGGGAGGGUGUUGGCUUGGCUUUUAACCUGUGGGGAUUUUGUCCAACAAGGAGUGGAAUGAUUUCAGAGCUGCCCUGAGGCUGGCACCCUGGUCACAGGAACCCUCUGCGCUGGCUCCUGUCUCAGUCCCCUCUGUAGAGUUAGAUCAGAAGACACAGAAAGUUCUGUGGCCAUGAAAGAUACCAGCUUGGAAGGGUUGUGUCUUCAGUGGCACCCUCAGAAAAAUUGUCUUAAAGCAAAGAGGUACCUGGCUCCAGACAAUUUUUCUGAUGAAAACAAAGUCUCUGCCCCGUCCCCACCCUGCCACCCUGGCAAAGUUACUUCCUUUACAGCUGCCCAGUGUACCAUAGACCAGACCCCAGGUCAGCAUUUGUCAAGAGCAUGGCUGCUGAGUCCCCUGUGGCAGUCAAUGCACUGUUUACCAAAUGCAGGUUUCUGUUCUCCCUCCCCAGCAAGACCUGCUGAACCCAGAUCUCUGGAAUGGGGCCCUAGGAAUUUGCAUUUCAACCUGCUUCCCAGGUGGCCCUGAUGCACCCCAGUAUUAGAGUUUAUUGCUAAAAGGAACAUGCCCUGUCACUCCUGGUAUCCUGGGAGUCAUGUUUCUCUUCUCUCUCAGUUCUACUUGGAGCAAGAGCUUUCCUGGGCUGCAAAUGAGAAAACAAUUCCUAGGAACCCACAGCAGUACUGAGCAUGCUGGGAGCUUGGGACUUGGAGAUGAAUGAGCCACCGUUGCUGCUCCAAGUAGGACUACUUGGAGUGUAGCUGAGGCCUUGGACGCAGUAUGACCAGGGGCAGCUCUGCCAGGGCUGUUGGCCAAUCAGUCAUUUUCAUUUCUUGUUGGAGGCCAGGUCCUCUGCUGAACUCAUUUCCUAGCUAGUGUUACCCUAAUUCUGAUGAAGAUCAAUGGGGCUAUAAUUCUUGUUUUUGUUCCUCUUUGCAGCAUUAACAGCAGCAAAGUUGUACCCCGGUUUGAAAGGUUUGGCUUGGGCGUCCUGGAGUCCAGUAAUCCAAAGAUGUAGCCAGCCAUAUGGUUUUUCGCUGCUGAUCUCUUUCUUUUUAAAAUGUGUUUCUGAAACAUCCCAACAACCACCACGACAAAAAAACACUGCCUGCCCAGCGCUGCAAACCAGGAGCACACGUCCUAGAUUCAGACUGUUGGCCAUAAACCCCACUCGGGAGAUGGAGCUGCACCUGCUAUUUCUUAAAAUGACACCACCAACAACCAAACCUGUCAUGACAGACAGCAAAUGUUUACACGUAUAUUUCUCCUGAGUGAACCUGAUGUUUUACAAUAGGUAAUAAUAAAAACAGUCUGUGCAGAUGCACUGGCACUGACGGCCAGGAUGGCGGAAAUGGCCAUCCCCUCUGAGGACCUUGUAGGCGGUGAGGGACCCAUGCUGGGCCAGAAGGAAGACAAACAUGGUAAUUGCAGCUGUUCUUGGGGUAGGGCGGGGAGCCCAGAAGGUCUGAUCUGGCCUCUGCUUUUUGGCCCAAGACUCCAUCAGGGAAAUCUAUCUAGGGCUCUCCCCUUGUCCUUUCAAAGGGAUACUGCCCCUUCCUCGUCUUGCAGAGGAAACCCUGGCUAGGAACUGAGCUAGUUUAUGGAGUCUGGAAUUCCUGGAGAGCUUGGGUUCACCUUCUCACCCCUGUAAUCCAGGCUGCUCCUGCUGGAAAAGUAGAAACAGAAUCCAAAAAAGGUCUGGACUCACCCGGUGGUUCCCAGCCAGGGUUUCUGCUGCAAGGUGAGGAAACAUCCAUGGCUUGUACAGAUGUGAGUCUUUGAUGAAGCCCCCAGGCAGGCACCAAGGUGAUGGGACUCAGGGCCUUGGCUUUUAGAUACAUCCCAGUCCCUGACUGACAUCUGACCAUGAGGGCUGGAUGGGUGGGAACAAGGAGGAGUAGAUGGCAAAAGUACCUGAGCCCACUUCCCAGCCACAGGGUGACCCUGGCACUGUAAAAACCCUUUGUCAGUCAUGCCAGAAGGUUCUAGAACUGCCCACCUCUUCCAUUUCAGUCCUGCUGAAACCCCUUAGCCUAUUUCCGACUCCUCUGUCCAUGCUCUGAGUUCAGCUGGGCAGUGUGUGGGCUAUCACCCCUUUCAUUUAGACCUACCUAGCUGGCCCCCAUCUGCAGAGCCUUCCUUAGCACCAUUAGGCCUUCUACUUGUGUCCAUUUGAAGCAGGAGGGGCUGGAUUUGGAAAAGUCUUUGAAGUGAGAGCACCACGCUUGUCUUCGUUAGAAACUCUUAACUGCAGAAAAAAGUUCCAGAUGGCAAGGGAGCCCUUAAGUGGAGAUUAGGUUGCAUUAGACUCCAAAACCAGAAAGGAAAAAGGGUGAUGGGAGUGGAGACGUGAUUGGAUUCAGGCCCAGAACCUGUGACCAUGCUCUGAGCUCAGACUUGGGGAGGGAGGGGUGUGGCUCCCACCCCUUCCAGUUAAGACCUGCCUAGCAGAGCCCCAGUCUCCAGCCCCUUCCCUAGCACCAGAGUCUGGUCAAAAUGCCACAGAAAAUGAGCUGCUCUGCCAGCAAGCUGUGGAGCUGCCUCCUCUCCAGGCCUGGCAUCCCUUGGUCAGCCCCUCCUGGGAGGGCACAGCCGUAUUACAGUGCCAGUGUGCCUGGCCAUCAGCAUCUUCACCCUUCCCAGUCUGUGUGGGGAGGCUGUAAACCCCGUGGAUUCAGCUCCGUGUGGAGUUUCUGUGCUAUGGUGGGACUGCUCAUUUUGCCCCAUCAUCCCUUUGGCCUCCCACACACCUGCCCCUUCCCAGGGAUCACGUGUGUCUCCAGCCUUUCACCUUUCUAUUGCAAUGGUGGCCUUUGUCCAGGCAAGAGCAGGCCUGAUGGAUGUACUGGUGAGCCCCACAGUUGGAUGUCAGCUCAGCCGUCCAACUGGGAGGAACAGUAGGCUCAGUUCCUCCCUGACCCCUGACACCAGGCCGCAGUGGGCAUGCACAGGCCCACAGAAAGUCAGUCUGGGUUUUGCUUUUCUCGUGAGCAUCACAGUUAAAGAAGCGCUCAUUGAGCAACUACAGUGCACUUGGUCUUCUGCAAGUGCUGGGCACCUAGAGAUAGGAACAGUCAUGGUCCCUGCUCUUAAGGAACUGAUGACCUGGUGGGGCCCUGUUGUCUUCAAGGAACCCAGAAGCCACUGGGCCCCAAAGGUGGAACUGAAGGACUGGGGGCAGCUGGCUCUCAGCCUGCCACCUCUGCACUGCCUGCCUUUAAAGAACCCCACCCCACCCCAUGAUGGCCCCCUCUGUUCCCCUUGUAUUUCAGUGACUGUGAAUUGAGGUUAGGAAGGCACACCUGCCCUUCUGUGUGCUCUCUCCACACGAAGGAUGACAGAUACUGUGAAUUCAGCCCUCACGGCCAACUGUGAAGGGGAUGGAGAAGGCUGGGAGGGCUCGGGGAGAGCUCUUAGGGGCUGCGGAAGUCCCCACGGGGGUCUGAGAGUGGAGCCCAAGCUUUGGCCCUCCAGGCAUCCCCAGUUUCCAGCCUCACCUCUGAAGCCCUGCUGCCUUUAACCACCAGAGCCGCAGCCCCCUGGGUUUCUGUCUAACUCGAAGUCUUGAAUCCUAGCUAGUUUGGGGUUGUGAGCAGUGUGUAGCAAAGUUGAUCUCUCCAUGUCACCAAAUCAAAACACCCUCUGUCAUCCUACGGCAUUUCCUCUUGAGGUCACAGAGAGGAAUGGCAAGCCCUGGAAACCUGUGUUAUUCUGUGUUGAUUUGGUGUGGGGGGAGGGUGGAGACGUAAAUGUGAAGCCAGUUGGAGUUUGUGCUAUGCAGCAGUGUUAGCCAGGAUCUCAUCAGCGUGCAAACCUAGCAUCUUCUGUGGCCACAAGCCACACACUUGCUUUUUUUGAAUGUGAUGUAAAAUUUGUACAGUAAAGUUUUUAUAUUUUCUAUCAACUACAUUUGUCUUCCAGACAUGCUAUUAAUUUAAAUUAAAAUGGUUAGUAUUAACAAACAUGCUGUAUCGGGUUUUUUUGCCACUGGCAAGAACAUGCCCUCUGUGCUAAGCCAGGCCUGGGUGUCUGGAGUUUGUGAAUAAAGUUAUACCAAGGUG